AGCGCCGGGGACGCGGCCUCAGCAGGGGCGCCCCGCCACGGGGAGCAGCCCAGGCGCUCGCCCCAGGACGUUGUCCGGCGGGCUGGGCUGGGACCCCUCUGCCUCCAGGGCGCGUCGGGAGCAGCAGGGAUCGGUGCCGCGCCGUGAGGGUGCGCAGAGGCUGCCCUCGGGCCCGCUACCCACAGACCCUCCGCGGGGCAGCGUCUCCGGGCCGGCCGCGCCCUGGUCCGCCGACCGCAGACGACUUGUGACACGGACGGCGCGUCCUGCUGACCCCAGCCGGCGCCGAGGGCUUGGAAUCUCGAGCGGGAAAAGACUACCAUGGCUGCAGGAGUCUUGCCUCAGAAUGAACAACCAUAUUCUACCUUGGUGAAUAACAGCGAGUGUGUUGCAAACAUGAAAGGAAAUUUAGAACGUCCAACACCAAAGUACACAAAAGUAGGGGAGCGUUUACGGCAUGUCAUUCCUGGACACAUGGCAUGUUCCAUGGCGUGUGGCGGUAGAGCUUGCAAGUAUGAGAACCCAGCCCGCUGGAGUGAGCAGGAGCAAGCCAUUAAGGGGGUUUACUCAUCCUGGGUCACUGAUAAUAUACUGGCCAUGGCCCGCCCAUCCUCUGAGCUCCUGGAGAAGUACCACAUCAUUGAUCAGUUCCUCAGCCAUGGCAUAAAAACAAUAAUCAACCUCCAGCGCCCUGGUGAGCAUGCUAGCUGUGGGAACCCUCUGGAACAAGAAAGUGGCUUCACAUACCUUCCUGAGGCUUUCAUGGAGGCUGGCAUUUACUUCUACAAUUUCGGAUGGAAGGAUUAUGGUGUAGCGUCUCUUACUACUAUCCUAGAUAUGGUGAAGGUGAUGACAUUUGCCUUACAGGAAGGAAAAGUAGCUAUCCAUUGUCAUGCAGGGCUUGGUCGAACAGGUGUUUUAAUAGCCUGUUACUUAGUUUUUGCAACGAGAAUGACUGCUGACCAAGCAAUUAUAUUUGUGCGGGCAAAGCGACCCAAUUCCAUACAAACCAGAGGACAGCUCCUCUGUGUAAGGGAAUUUACUCAGUUUCUAACUCCUCUCCGCAAUAUAUUCUCUUGCUGUGAUCCCAAAGCACAUGCUGUCACCUUACCUCAAUAUCUAAUUCGCCAGCGUCAUCUGCUUCAUGGUUAUGAGGCACGACUUCUGAAACACGUGCCAAAAAUUAUCCACCUAGUUUGCAAAUUGCUGCUGGACUUAGCGGAGAACAGGCCAGUGAUGAUGAAGGAUGUGUCCGAAGGACCUGGUCUCUCUGCUGAAAUAGAAAAGACAAUGUCUGAGAUGGUCACCAUGCAGCUGGAUAAAGAGUUACUGAGGCAUGACAGUGAUGUGUCCAACCCGCCUAACCCCACUGCAGUGGCAGCAGAUUUUGACAAUCGAGGCAUGAUUUUCUCCAAUGAGCAACAGUUUGACCCUCUUUGGAAAAGGCGGAAUGUUGAGUGCCUUCAACCCCUGACUCAUCUGAAAAGGCGGCUCAGCUACAGUGACUCAGAUUUAAAGAGGGCCGAGAACCUCCUGGAGCAAGGGGAGACUCCACAGACAGUGCCUGCCCAGAUCUUGGUUGGCCACAAGCCCAGGCAGCAGAAGCUCAUAAGCCAUUGUUACAUCCCACAGUCUCCAGAACCAGACUUACACAAGGAAGCCUUGGUUCGCAGCACACUUUCUUUCUGGAGUCAGUCAAAGUUUGGAGGCCUGGAAGGACUCAAAGAUAAUGGGUCACCAAUUUUCCAUGGAAGGAUCAUUCCAAAGGAAGCACAGCAGAGUGGAGCUUUCUCUGCAGAUGUUUCAGGCUCACACAGCCCUGGGGAGCCAGUUUCACCCAGCUUUGCAAAUGUCCAUAAGGAUCCAAACCCUGCUCACCAGCAAGUGUCUCACUGUCAGUGUAAAACUCAUGGUGUUGGGAGCCCUGGCUCUGUCAGGCAGAACAGCAGGACACCCCGAAGCCCUCUGGACUGUGGCUCCAGUCCCAAAGCACAGUUCUUGGUUGAACAUGAAACCCAGGACAGUAAAGAUCUGUCUGAAGCAGCUUCACACUCUGCAUUACAGUCUGAAUUGAGUGCUGAGGCAAGAAGAAUACUGGCGGCCAAAGCCCUAGCAAAUUUAAAUGAAUCUGUAGAAAAGGAGGAACUAAAAAGGAAGGUAGAAAUGUGGCAGAAAGAGCUUAAUUCCCGAGAUGGAGCUUGGGAAAGAAUAUGUGGCGAGAGGGACCCUUUCAUCCUAUGCAGCUUGAUGUGGUCUUGGGUGGAGCAACUGAAGGAGCCUGUAAUCACCAAAGAGGAUGUGGACAUGUUGGUUGACAGGCGAGCAGAUGCCGCAGAAGCACUUUUUUUAUUAGAGAAGGGACAGCACCAGACUAUUCUCUGCGUGUUGCACUGCAUAGUGAACCUGCAGACAAUUCCCGUGGAUGUGGAGGAAGCUUUCCUUGCCCAUGCCAUUAAGGCAUUCACUAAGGUUAAUUUUGAUUCUGAAAAUGGACCAACAGUUUACAACACCCUGAAGAAAAUAUUUAAGCACACGCUGGAAGAAAAAAGAAAAAUGACAAAAGAUGGCCCUAAGCCUGGCCUCUAGCUUUCACUCGUGGUGAAUAUUUCAGACCUAAAGAUCCAGAUAGUAUCUCUGUUCAUAUGUGAAUAAGUUGAAGAUUGUGGGGCUACUUUUUCUCAUAGCACUUUAUUUUGAAUGUUGUUAGUUUGUGCUGAGAAUGGUCGUCCGUAUUUGAACCAAUUAUUUAUUUUAAAAUAUAUUUAAGCUACAUUUUUGUUUUGAAAAAUUGCCAUAAAUUUGGUGCCACUUUCUUUUAUUUAUUUGACUGAGUUAAUAUUAUUGUAUUAACAUUUUAAGUAUAUGGUGUUUACAUUCUUAUUUCUUUUGACAUUUUGGAAAUAAUCAUAACUUGUCUUUCCAAAAUAACCAUUUUCUUGAUGGAACUCUUCCUAGAGUUUUUACCAAAUAGCUAACUUUAGUAGUAAAACCUCAUUGUGUAUCCAUUCCCCCACAGAUGAACUAAGAAAGUCACCAAGUGUCUUAAGCUGUUUUAUAUUUGUUACGAAGAAGGCUAUUGCUACAAUAUUUUUAAAGGUUUCUUUUUUAACUUUGAAAUUUUUUGUUUUUCCUUUUCUUUUUAUAAAUGUAACAGAGGGUUUCAAAGCAUAUUAUUUUUCAGAGAGAUUUAGUUUUACUUUAAUGGAGUGACUGUGAAGUGGUUGGGAUUUUUUGCUUGUAGAAAGUAGACUUGCUCUUUGUCAGAUUUCCAAACAACCUUGCCAGCCUUGGCUGUCAAAAGGAGGCAGGAGCAGUUCUCAACACACCAAGCCUUAUUCCCACUCCCUUGGGUUGCUGCUGAGCCAAAUAGCAUCUUUACAGAGGAAGUGGGAUCAGAGGCAGGAAGUGUGGAAAGUUGCUAAGAAGCAGGGCUUGCCUCUGUCCUCCCGGGGACUCCACAGGGAUAUUCGUGCAGGGCAGGGGCUCUGUGCCAGCCCUGCUCUCUCAGAUGCCACAGCCACUCUGCAGAGGUGACUCUUGGAGCUGGAGGAAGUCAAAACUGGGCCACUGUUUGUACUGAUGGUGUAUUAGCAUGAGCAGCGUGGCCCUGGCCCCACACUCCCAAAUCUGCCACUCCAUAGACCCACUUGCCUCAAGGCUUUAUAUUUGGCUGCUUUCUUACAAUGAGAAUUAAGAUUUUUAAACUGAAGUUGACCAUACAGGUUGCAUUAGCCCUAACUGGCUUCAUGUAAGAAGGGUGACUGCCUAAACUAGUUCCUUGUAAGCUGAACCAUCAAUUAUCAGUUGAAGCCAUACUUUUAUUUAAAUUAAUAUACGUAGAUACCAGAGGCCAAGCCACAGAGAGGAUAAUAGUUCUUCCCAAUAAAGGUGAUAUUAAUCAGACUAAUUUCGAACUAAAGAAGUUACUGCUUAAAGACGGAAUUUCAGGGGAAGCAAGACUCAUUUAGAACAAAUGAAAUUUCUCCAGUCCUACAUUUCUGAAUUGACUUCUAGCACAUCAAAAAUAUUUCAGUCAUUAUCAGUCUCAUUAACUGAAAUGCCAAAUGCUAAAUGCAGUGUUCUUUCACACUGUUUUAAUUUUCUUGGGAAAUUGAGUCCAGUGGAUGUUAAUGGAGUGGGUUGCCCAUCCCUGAAAUGUCUUAUUUUCAAGUGCCUGGCCUGGGAAAGAAGGGGAAGAAACAAUUGCAUUAUAUCCAAAGAUACACUAUAAAAAUAGAGUUUUUACCAAAAAAAGAUGUUUGUUCUCAUCUCAGUAGGCCUCAUUUGGGCAAGUGACCCACAGGUCUUUUGGCGAGUUUGCUAUUUGCCUGUUGAAAUACUUGUUUCAACUUAGAGAACAGUUAUGAUGUGACCAUAGCAUGGCACAACUAAAAAUCUAAGCCUGAAACCUGAAAAAAGAGAUAUGACAAGGGAAAUUAAUCAGGCUAUACAUAAGUAUUGUAUUUAUUUGAAUAAAAAUAAAAAGAGCAACCCA